ACACGCGCGCGCGCGCGGCUUCUCGGGGCCUUGCUGGCCUCCUCGGUUCUCUGGGGGACCCCGGCCGCUGCCUGCGGCCUUCUUCCAGGCGAGGCCCUGCUCGGGGUUCUUCCGGCCUCCCCCCAGGCAAAACCCGCAAGGAGCGGUUUCUGGCGUGGCUGGGUCCCCUGCGGCGGAAGGGCGCCUCCCGGCCACGCUCGCUGUAGUGAAGGAGCGCGGCAGCCUGGGGCUCGUUUGGGUGAUUUCCCUCGGCGGUGGAGGUCGCUCCUAAUAGAGGCGGCGGCGGAUCACCCGAACAGCCUUCAGGUGCUUCCCUGCUGACCUCUUUUUAACGUGUCACUCCAUGGAUUCCUUUGGGCAACCCAGACCAGAAGAUAAUCAGUCAGUAGUCAGAAGAAUGCAAAAGAAAUACUGGAAAACUAAACAGGUCUUUAUCAAAGCAACAGGAAAAAAAGAGGAUGAGCACUUGGUGGCGUCUGAUGCUGAACUGGAUGCUAAACUUGAGGUUUUUCACUCUGUUCAAGAGACAUGCACUGAACUUCUGAAGAUAAUCGAGAAAUACCAGCUAAGACUCAAUGUUAUAUCAGAGGAAGAAAAUGAGCUAGGGCUCUUUUUAAAAUUUCAAGCAGAACGGGAUGCAACUCAAGCUGGCAAAAUGAUGGAUGCCACUGGCAAGGCACUUUGUUCUUCAGCCAAGCAAAGAUUGGCCCUGUGUACUCCUCUGUCUCGUCUGAAGCAAGAAGUAGCAACAUUCAGUCAAAGGGCAGUAUCUGAUACCUUGAUGACAAUUAAUCGGAUGGAGCAGGCACGCACAGAAUACAGAGGAGCUCUACUGUGGAUGAAAGAUGUAUCCCAAGAGCUGGACCCAGACACCUUAAAGCAAAUGGAAAAGUUUAGAAAAGUACAGAUGCAAGUGAGAAAUAGCAAAGCUUCUUUUGACAAGUUAAAGAUGGAUGUUUGUCAGAAAGUGGAUUUACUUGGAGCUAGUCGCUGCAAUAUGCUAUCUCAUUCGCUCACUACCUACCAGAGAACACUGCUUGGAUUCUGGAAGAAAACAGCUCGAAUGAUGUCCCAAAUUCAUGAAGCCUGUAUUGGCUUUCAUCCGUAUGAUUUUGUAGCUCUCAAGCAACUACAAGACACGCCAAGCAAGAUUAGUGAAGACAAUAAAGAUGAACAAAUAGGCGGUUUUCUUACUGAACAGCUCAAUAAGCUAGUUUUGUCUGAUGAGGAAGCAAGCUUUGAGAGUGAACAAGCAAACAAAGAUCACAAUGAAAAACAUUCUCAAAUGAGAGAAUUUGGAGCACCUCAGUUUUCUAACUCUGAAAAUGUUGCAAAAGAUCUACCUGUAGAUUCAUUGGAAGGAGAAGAUUUUGAGAAGGAAUUCUCAUUUCUGAACAACCUCCUAAGUUCUGGUUCUUCAAGUACUAGUGAAUUUACCCAAGAAUGCCAGACUGCCUUUGGGAGCCCCAGUGCCAGUCUCACAUCCCAGGAGCCUUCCAUGGGGUCUGAGCCCCUCGCUCAUUCUUCUCGAUUCCUUCCUUCACAACUCUUUGACCUUGGCUUUCAUGUGGCUGGAGCGUUCAACAACUGGGUCUCCCAAGAGGAAUCAGAACUUUGUCUUUCACACACUGAUAACCAGCCAGUGCCUUCACAGAGUCCAAAGAAAUUAACAAGAUCCCCCAACAAUGGCAACCAAGACAUGUCAGCCUGGUUCAAUCUGUUUGCAGACUUGGAUCCACUUUCAAACCCAGAUGCUAUUGGACACUCAGAUGAUGAACUUCUUAAUGCUUGACUGAAGUUAUAAUGUCACUUCAGUGGCCUUGAGACAUCAAUUUUGCAACGUAUUUCCUUCGUGGAAAGGAUUUAGAUUGUAACCCGCACACAAAAGCACGGUGUUUGUGAAUAUAACACCUGUCAGCCAACUUUAGACAGAUGGUAAAGACCACAUUUGAAUAAGUACACAUCUUUCAUAUCUUGGAUUUGCAGCUGUUGGUACUAUGUGGAAAAUAUUAGAAACUUCUAUGUGGAAAAUAUUAGAAACUACAGAGUUUGCGAUAUUUAGAUACUGAAAUUUAUGUCAAAAUAACGGCUAGGAAUAAUUCUGUCAAUAUGGAGUUGAGCUUAUUUCUUUGGAAACCCUUUUAAGUUGCCUUGCUGGCUGUGAGAAUUUUAUAUGUGGAUAACAAAGAUAGAUAGAUAGCAUGUAAAUUGGGUUGUGGUUUGGGGUCAGUUUUUAAAUGAAAUAGUAGCGAGGAGGAUUUUCUGUUUUGGAAAACACCAUUAGAACCAGACCAGCUUUGUUUUGGGUUAGAGAGAGUAAGAUUUGAGAACUCAGUUUGCUUUAAUGAAAUCACAGAGAAACUUGGUACUUGUUUUUCUUCAUUUGGAGGCUAAAAUGUAAUGUUUUUUCAUUCAUACAAAAUAAUGGACACUCCCUAAUUCCAUUAUUAAAUCUUGAAGGGGAAGUAGCAGGAUAAUUAAUUUGCUAAGCCCAUCCUCUGCAGAAACAGAAAAAUCUAUCUUCCCAUCUCCUAAAACUCAGAAUGCACAGUAAUACUUAAGGCUUGUACAAGUGUCUUCAGACCCACUUUUUCAUACACUUGCUAUAUAGUAGUAUGCAGUAUUUAUAUUAUUCCUGAAAAUAAAAUGAGGGGAGAAUAUUCCCUAAGCAACUGGCAAUAGUAUUCCUGAAAUACCUAGAAAUUUCUAUCUGAAUGAGGGAGACACUUAUGAACACCUUAUCCUUACAUAUAUUUGCAUACUUAUCUCAUAUUUUGUGACAUAAUUAUUUAACCCAGAAUACUUUCUGGCAGACAUACAGAAAGCUCUGUGUGAUCAAUAAGGGAGUGUCUCAUUUUUCUACUUCCCUCUUUCUGUGGGUGACAUGAUCUGAGGUUCUAUUUGAUUACUAAGCAAAAUCUGUUACCCCUACAGGGUUUAGAACCUAAGUAUUAGAGAGGAAGGCUAUUUAAUGGAAGUUAGUGUAAGCUGAUAAAAACGUAGCUACCGUACACACACAUCAAUCACUCAAUUUCCUGUCCUUUUAAAUUGCCCACCCUUUAAUUUUGAAGCAAUUUCCCAAGUGUGUGUUUGUUUUAUAUUUGUCAUCCAGUCCAUUGCAUUUCCAUAAGAAGACAUUUUGACUGGCUGGGUGCGGUGGCUCACGCUUGUAAUCCCAGCACUUUGGGAGGCUGAGGCAGGCGGAUCACGAGGUCAGGAGAUGGAGACCAUCCUGGCUAACAUGGUGAAACCCCGUCUCUACUAAAAAUACAAAAAAUUAGCCAGGCGUGGUGGCACGUGCCUGUAGUCCCAGCUACUCCGGAGGCUGAGGCAGGAGAAUGGCGUGAACCCGGGAGGCGGAGCUUGCAGUGAGCUGAGAUGGCGCCACUGCACUCCAGCCUAGGCAACAGAGCAAGACUCCGUCUCAAAAAAAAAAAAAAAAAAAAAAGACAUUUUAACUAAGUUAUUCACAGUAGCUUCCAUGUGCUCUUAGUUCUAUUCUAAACAGGCUUAUUUAGAAAAGGAUUGCUUGUAAUGUUUGUCAUGGUACAUAGAAAACAUUGGACCAGAGUAGGUAAAAUGCAGUCCAUGUCCCAUCCAUAGCCAUCUACAAUAGUAACUGCCCACAGGCUCUCCAGAAAACUACUACAAUGGCCAAGUACAGUAUAGGCUGGAAAGACCUUAUCUGAAGGUCAGAAACAUUGACUCAGAAAAAAGGUAUGAAGUCUUUCCAUAAAAUCUUUUCACAAUAUUACUCCUAUUUCUUUUAGAUUUUAAUGAGCCAUUACUUAUCUCUUCAGAAGACUUAAGUCUUCCUUUAUACUCAGUGAAAUUUCCCAGAAUGUAAUACUGUCACUGUUCUGCCAAGUUCCAAUCACCAAGAUCAUGAUUACGAAUCCCAAUCUGAAUUCUAUACCCAUGGUGACUCUGAUGCUCUCAACUUUUGAGUGCCUCAAAAAAUGCUAAAACUUUGGCUGGGCAUGGUGGCUCACGCCUGUAAUCCCAGCACUUUGGGAGGCCAUGGCGGGUGGAACAUUUGAGGGCAUGAGUUCGAGACCAGCCUGGCCAACAUGGUGAAACCCUGUCUCUACUAAAAAUACAAAAAUUAGCCAGGUGUGGAGGUACAUGCCUGUAAUCCCAGCUACUCAGGAGGCUGAGGCAGAAGAAUUGCUUGAACCCAGGCGGCAGAGGUUGCAGUGAGUCGAGAUUGCACCACUACACUCCAGCCUGGGCAACAGAGAGCGACUCUCUCAAAAAAAAAAAAAAAAAAAAAAAAAAAAGCUAACUUUAUGUCUUGAGAGUUUGUACCAUUUUUCUUUGUAGUGGUCACCUUGCUAAUGCAUUAGUUCUGAGAUAUUUAUCUCCCUCACAUGUGUGCAAGGAAGUCCCUGUUAUCGAAUACAGAUACUUUAACAAGCAGACAAAGCAGAAACCCAAAGUCCAUACUAGGAACACCCUAAAUUUUCCAAAAGCAAAAGUUCUCCCGAAAUGGAGACAUACAAGGGACUUUUAUUAUUCUGUUACUAGUUUCUAUAACAUUUCUUCUUUCAACAGAGUAUAUGUUUCCCAUUUAACCCAGAGCAACAUUAACUUCCUUAGCAAGUCCAGUUCUAACUUCCAACAAGUCCAACCACUGUUUUUGAAGAGCAUAUCAGUAACUAUAUUAAGAUGAAGGUAACCACAUUCGUAUUUUCUCAAGAUUAGUUAUUUGAAGCUCAGCAGUUUUUGUGGUCAGAAAGAAAUUUUGCUCUAUUAAACCAAUACUGCUAAUAUAAAAAACCACCACACUGAAGAAACGAGGGAAAGGACGGGAUAAGCACAGAACAGAGAAUGACUGGUUGCUUUUUGUCUCAAUCUAGAUAAUCCAUUCAAUAAGAAGUAAAUUAAUUAUCCUUAACCAAUGGUAGGCUGAGAACAACCCUCAAAAUAGAUAUUUUUUAUGUUAAAUGGGGAGAAAUAUCUAUACUUUAUGUUAUACUGGAUAAAAAUGUGUUUUAAGUCUAAAAAAAACCAGACGAGCUAAACUUUGCCUAGUGUGUCUACAACCAUUUUUUAGGAGACGCAGGAAUACCAGGGCAUAAUAAGAUCAGAUUGGUGUAAUUUUGUAUGUUUUUGAAAUCCUUCAUUAAUUGUAGAACCUUGAUAUGAUUAGAAACAAACUGUAUUUCAACAAACAGGUUUCAGUAUUUGCACACUGAAAAAGUGUUUUGUAUUUUAACUAUAAAUAUUUCACGUAUCUGUAUAGACCAUCUAGAAAUGUAGAGGUCUUACAGCAUUAGAACGAAGGAAGUUUACAUGUGCUCUAUCUAUUUUUCUGAGCCUCUUUUAAUAAAGAUUGCAAGAAGGCAUAAAACAAGAGUUUGUUUCCUGAAGUUUUUAGUACAAUUAUUGUUUUCCUAUUCAAAAACUUGGGUUUUACCUCAAGAUCAUAGUAUUAGGAAAGUACAUUGAGUUGAUACGGACAUGGGAGAACGAAAAUAAAACCAGGGCAAUUAAUAUCCUUGUAAGGCCAGGCGCGGUAGCUCACGCCUAUAUAACAGCACUUUGGGAGGCCAAGGCAGGCAGAUCACUUGAAGUUGGGAGUUUGAGACCACCCUGGCCAACAUGGUGAAACCCCAUCUCUAUGAAAAAUAUAAAAAUUAGCUGGGCAUGGUGGCAGAUGCCUGUAAUCCCAGCUACUUGGGAGGCUGAGGCAGGAGAAUCGCUUGAACCCGGGAGGUGGAGGUUGCAGUGAGCUGAGAUCAGGCCAUGCACUCCAGCCUGGGUGACAGAGUGAGACUCCGUCUCAAAAGAAAAUCCUUGUGAGAUGAAUUCGUUCUUAUUUCAUAUACAAGGGGACUAUGUAAGAUAUGGGAAAUAAUAUAAUGUACGUUAUUUAUGUAAAUACUUUCAGUAACAAAAACUAACAAAUAUCAAAAAUCUGAGCCUAGACACAAACAAUUAAAUAUAAGCCAUAGUAUGUAACCUGACUUAUUGAAGGCAGGAAUAAAAAGAAGAGAGCCAGAAUUGAUUCAGUUAUUUUUGUCUUCCAUAGUGUUGGCAGGGCCCUGCAUUUCUCUACCUUGAGCAAUGAAGCAGUCCCAGAAUUUUGGAAUAUAGAAAUUAGGAAGGAAAAACGAACUUUAAAAUAUUAAUUUAGUAGAACUGAAAGUAAUGCAUUUCAUGCAACAGUAAAGUGCUUAAACAUGGCAAAGAAAACUAAGGGACAAGAUAAGAAAAAUGGUUGGUAAAGAUGGGUCACAUCCAGAAGCCCAACAUAAGCUAUUUUUCCAUCUUUUUCUGUACCAUUUAAAAGACUACUAAAGAGUUCAAAACAAACUGUCCUUGGCAUUUAAAGUCAAAACAUGGUUCUUCACUCAGUGGUGUAAAUUAACUACUCAUUGGCCAAAGAGUAAAUACAAAAAGGAGAUGAAGUUCUGACUGGUGUUGUGGGUGAGAUUUUGCAGUGUAUGUUUUUACAUUUGUAGUGUACGUUUUAAACUUCCGGUUUUCUUGCUGCCUCAACAUCUCCACAAACAGGCUGUGAGCACCUGGCCCAGUGUGAUAUGGGUGGCCCCUGCCACAAGUUUCCCUUGCUACCUUGCCCAUGACCUAGUAACAUUUAAAUGCACCAGUGAAAUUCUCUUUUUCUUGUGUGCUUCUCCCUGACCCAAAGGCUCCUGCCCAUGUCUUAGGCCUCUCCGCUCCCCACCUGCUUGGCUGAGCCCCCUCCCAUGUGACCCCCUCUCAGCAUGCAGUGACUGGUCUCUCUAGGACCUGUGAGUAUAUUACAACUUUUUUUCCUGUGUCUCUCCUGUGAUAUCUCUUGUGGCUAAACCUCACUGACCAUAACCUAAAAAAACACAUACAAAAAACAUGAAAGAAAAAGUUGUUUCUUGAGCUGGCCUGGACGAACGGGGAGCCAGGGGCUCGACCCUGGCUGUUGGAGGCGCAGUGAGGCCUGGUCUCCGGCUGCCAGACCACGCUGAGCGGAGCGCGCGGCAGGCUCGCCUCAGCGCUGCGGGGAACGCGCGCGCCGCCGUCCGCGGUCGCCCGUAGGUGCCUGCACGCGUCGGGGUCACGGCCUUUGGCCGACAGGAGCGAGAAGACUCAGGAGCCGCCCCGCGCCUUCGAUCCGGCGCUGCUGGAGUUCCUGGUGUGCCCGCUCUCCAAGAAGCCGCUCAGAUAUGAAGCAUCAACAAAUGAAUUGAUUAAUGAAGAGUUGAGAAUAGCUUAUCCAAUCAUUGAUGGGAUUCCUAAUAUUAUCAUAUUAGGCAGCUAGGAUGACACAUCAAAGAAGCAAGAAGUGGAGCAGCGCUAGUUCAUAAUUUAAAAAAAUAAAACAGCCAACUCUUCUUAGUACCAUAUACCUUUUAAAACACAGUGGCAAGUAAUAAGCGGAAGAGAAGAAUCUUUCUGUCUCUUUCUACGUUGACUGUUCUUAUUCCACUGGUUUAUUUAGCAGGACUGUUCCACUCAGCCUCUGUAGAAGAAAACUUCCCACAGGGCUGCACUUGCACAGCUAGCCUUUGCUUUUACAGCCUGCUCUUGCCUAUUACCAUACCGGUGUAUGUAUUCUUCCACCUUUGGACCUGGAUGGUUAUUAAACUCUUCAUGCAUAACUGAUGCAACUAGAGUCAAUAUGCUGUAUAUAUUAAUGAUAGCUCUUGGGCAUCUAUCUCUGAAAGCUCAAAUGGAUGGAAUUUAGUUUGUGGGAAAGAGGCUUUGCUUUGAGCAUAUCAGGCUUAGGACUGUGGACGGCUUAAGUUGCAGACGCUUCUUUUAUUGUACUCUUGUUCUGCCCGUGUUUUUUGAAGGCUCUGACAUAACUGCUUUAUCAGAAGAAACAUUUUGACAGUGUCUUGUUGGAGAUAAACAUCCCUAAUUGACAUGUGAUGACUACUUCUUAUUCCAUUCAUCUAAGAGUCAUUGAAAUUUUGUUUUCUUUGUUUGUUUAGCUUCAAGGUCUUUGGUAGUCACAUGUUAGGGAUGACUGAAAUAAUUCCAAAGGAGUGAUGUUGGAAUAGUCCCUCUAAGGGAAAGAAAUGCAUUUGAACGAAUGUGAUAUAAAACCACAUAAUCAAAUAGAAAUUUCAUGUACUUACAAAAAUUUAGUUUGUAAAAUUACCUUCAUUUCUUUGACAUUAAAUGCUUAUAUUAGCAAUAAAGA